AGUCUCAGCGCGCCUGCGCCGAGCGGCCCUGCGCGCAGUGAGGCAGUGGCGGGGGAAGGCACCGGUGGGGCCGACGGGCGGGUUGAAGGAGGGAAGCGGGCGAGCGAAGUCCCAGUGCGCGCCGCGGCAGCCCGGGCACCCUCCCCUUCCGGGCGUGAGUCGCUGUGAAAAGAGCUGAAGCGAGCGGACUCGCACCGGCAGCGAGGCGCCGCUCCCGCCGCCUCAGCCCGGCCUUCCUCGGCUCCGGCGCUCCGGUCGCGGGGCCCGGGUUCCUCGGCACACCCCGCUCCAGCCGCCCCCAGAGCCUGUCCCCAGCCCUUCGGAAGCCCCGGCGCCAGCCCGGGCCCUCGGCAGGGAGGAUGACGGAGCUGCAGUCGGCACUGCUACUGCGAAGACAGCUGGCAGAACUCAACAAAAAUCCAGUGGAAGGCUUUUCUGCAGGUUUAAUAGAUGACAAUGAUCUCUACCGAUGGGAAGUCCUUAUUAUUGGCCCUCCAGAUACACUUUAUGAAGGUGGUGUUUUUAAGGCUCAUCUUACUUUCCCAAAAGAUUAUCCCCUCCGACCUCCUAAAAUGAAAUUCAUUACAGAAAUCUGGCACCCAAAUGUUGAUAAAAAUGGUGAUGUGUGCAUUUCUAUUCUUCAUGAGCCUGGGGAAGAUAAGUAUGGUUAUGAAAAGCCAGAGGAACGCUGGCUCCCUAUCCACACUGUGGAAACCAUCAUGAUUAGUGUCAUUUCUAUGCUGGCAGACCCUAAUGGAGACUCACCUGCUAAUGUUGAUGCUGCGAAAGAAUGGAGGGAAGAUAGAAAUGGAGAAUUUAAAAGAAAAGUUGCCCGCUGUGUAAGAAAAAGCCAAGAGACUGCUUUUGAGUGACAUUUAUUUAGCAGCUAGUAACUUCACUUAUUUCAGGGUCUCCAAUUGAGAAACAUGGCACUGUUUUUCCUGCACUCUACCCACCUAUUGCUGGACUUCUGUUGUACAAGUUGGCAAACACUGGCUGGAACUGGGCUGCAAUAAAACAUGCCAGUUAUCAAUGCUGACAAGAGCCUAACAAGUGCCAACUUACAGAUGAUUACGCAUUUUGAAUUCUAAUGAACUGUUUUAACCUUCAGGAAGAAUUGUAAAGACCUGUACAUAGCACAACAUGAUCCGGAUAAUAUAUAUACUGUUCAUGUACAUCCACAAAUACACCUUGUACCAAAUAAUGCUUUCUUGUAGUAGAAUAAGAAUCGUGUAAAUUCUAAGAGAUUUUAGCAGGUUUUCUUUCCUAUUCAUUGUUUCUUAUCAGUUUAAAAGGAUUCCUUUAAGCAUGUCAGAUGAAAAGCAAUUAGGAUUAAAAGUUUCCAUUUAAUUUCCCUUAAACCCUUGAGGCUUCAUUAAACUCUUUUCACUUACUAAACUUUUGUAUCUUCUUUGUUUUGACACACUCCCCUUUGCUUUUAUCUCUUACCUGCCAGAAUGUUCUCAAAUGAUUUAGUUCAAAUACUGAAAUACUUAAUGAGCAAUUACUUGAUUUUUAAUGAUGACUUCGAAGGAGUCAUCACUAGGUGCUUUGUCCUUUUUGUAUUCUAGUUGCACCCACCUCUUGGAUUGGAUAUAGCAAUAACAUUUAUUGGCCGUUGUGAGCUCUUGAUCCCAGUCAUUACCCCUGAGAACUAAAAAUAGAUGGUUCUUAAUUCAACUUACUGAAAAUUUCCCCAAACAAUAGCAAAUCUGACUUUUCCCUCUUCAGUUGCCUGGUAUUAAGGUUGGAUAAAUGAAGCAUGCACAGCUACAGGCUUUCUACUUAACUUCUGGGUUUGCUAUUACAAAUCCUAUUUACUCUCAUACCCUUCUCCUUAGUCCUUCAUAUUUCUCUGCCUCUAUUCUUCUAUACUGCAGAUUUUUCUCACCUAUUGUACAAAGAAAUUGCGAUGUAUAUUUUCAUGUAAUUUGAUUUUGGAAUUCUGUCACCUUAUGUAGUGAGUUCUUCCAAAAUAUAAUUUUUUUUCAAUAAUUGUCAAGUUGUUGGCUUUUAUUGUAUUGAAUGAAGGCUAUAAUACUGAGUGCCAGAGAAGUGGUUUAGGAAAAUCUCAGGUUGAUUCCUUAUGCAAAUGAACUUUUAAUACUUGAAAAUCACAUGGCCAUGGCAGUAUAUGUAUUUGGUUCUAUCUAGAUUCUUCUGUGAAUCUAAAAGCAUUACAGGGGUAAAUGCUUUGCUAUUUGACGUAUAGAUCCCGUCACUAACAAUAGUACACUUGGAUGUGAUUAAUGUUUGAGCUUCAAUAUAUUUCAUAUCAUACAGUUUUCUAAAACAACUUCAGCAAAUGGUAAAAUGAACAUGUGCAGUGUUAAAGGCAGGCCUUAGGCUCCUUCAUGUUUGUUGUGAGGUUGUGUGUGGGAAGUAGUCUUUGGCUUAUAAGGGAUAGAACUUGAGACAGUAGCAGAUGGGACAUGGUGUUUGAUUGUGAGAAUCAGUGAGAAUUCGUGCAUCUCUGCUCUGUGGGGUUUGGAGAAAUGCUUUGGCAGAAGAGUGAAAGAACUCCUGCCAAGAGCCCAGACCUCUACAAACGUUGUAUGUCCUUUUUUAAGCAGAAAUAAAAUGGUUGAGGAUGUAGUCACAGUAGAGAGUGAUUUUUUUCUAAGUCCCUGUCCUCUACUCUGAAGCGUUAUAAAAACCUGUAAACAUUAUACAAACCCACAAACCUUAUAGAAACUCGUAAGUGUGUUGUGACUGGAAAUUGAUUCAUUAGAACCCAGUUUUCUUUAAGAACUUUGUGACUUGGUUUUUUUUUUCCUUUUCCAAAGACUGUAAAAAUAGUUGCCCCAAAAUGUCAGCACUGCACACCCUCCAGGGACUUGGAAUACAAUCCUUUUUACUUUUUUUUUUUUUUUUUUAAGAAACUGGGUCUCUCUGUCACCCAGGCUGGAGUGCAGUGGCAACGAUCAUAGCUAACUGCAGCUUUGACCUCCUGGGCUCAAGUGAUCCUCCUGCCUCAGCCUCCUGAGUAGCUAGGACUACAGGUGUAUGCCACCAUGCCUGGCUAAUACAAAAAAAUUCUUUUAAGAGAUGGGAUCCCUCCCUUUUAAAAUCAGAACUUGUUCACAUGGUGGUUGCUUGUGGCAAAACGGAGUUCAAAUUUUGCUCUCCUAUUGCUAUAAUUCUGCUAGCAAUCUGUUGAGGUGAAACUUGGGAUCUGACUCUUCAGCAAGCAGCAAAUGACCUAGUAACUCAGGGACAACUAUUUUUGAACUUUAAGUGCCACUUUAAUGCAGUUAGUUUGAUAAAACCAUGUGGGUUUUUUUUUUAGGGCUAGCUCUACGGGAGUGGAAGUGAGAGCCAGGCAUGAGUGCGUCUCCACAUGCUUUUCCACCUGCCCUGAGUGUGUUACAUACUGAAACAGGCCUACAUAGAUGUUACAACUUCCCUUCCUCUGUCGGAGAUGUCAUCUGUGCCUUUCUCAGUGUUCAUCUGAUAAUGUAAAUUUAAAUGCCUCUACAUUUGAUACGAAACCCACAUUCAGGUGACACUGAACGAGGUGGCUUUUGUCCCACCAGUGCCUCAUCAGUGUGAGGCGAUUCCUCUCUGCUUUAGGAAAAUGAUUUUUCCCCCUAAACUUGUGCCAACCAUCAACAACAUCUCCAUAGAUCUUAUGGAUUGUAGAACUGUUGGCUGUUUCCUAAAUUUAUUCCAAGUUCUCGUAGAGGCAUAUAGAUUUCAGUCUGUGCUUGUAUGGGAUAGAUGAUCUGAGUGGCUUUCUGGCCUCUUUUUUGAGUUUAAAAUCCAUAUGAGGUUGACGUGUCAUACUAAGGUAACAUGUUUGUGAGGUUAUUCCACUAGUACUGUGAUCACGUGGGUGUCAGUAUCUUUAACGGCCUUCAUUCUUGGUUGUGAGAUUUUAUUUGAUAUGCCCACUCACCCUCGACGAAUCUGCCCGCUUUGGGCUGUGGUGCCUGUGUAUCUUUGCCCGUCUGGUCUCCAGUUGGUGGAAUUACCUUUUUUGUACUGCCACUUCUCAGCAUCUUUGAAAUUUGACAUAAUGUUGCUUCAUUUCAGUUUUUUUAGUUCUGUAAUUUGUUGAUUGUAUUUAACUAUGUGAGUUCUGUUGUGAUGUUUACUGUAUUGUAAAGCACCUCAUUCAUGUGAUGAGUGCUCUAUAAAUCAAUAAAUGAUGACUUAGAGGCUGUA